GGAUCCUUGCUGCAGCGUCAGCGCCGCCGCCCGUGCCUUUCCUCUUCCUCCUCCUCCUCCUUGGCAUCCGCCUCUUCUUCCUCCUGCGUCCUCCCCCGCUGCCUCCGCUGCUCCCGACGCGGAGCCCGGAGCCCGCGCCGAGCCCCUGGCCUCGCGGUGCCAUGCUGCCCCGGCGGCGGCGCUGAAGGAUGGCGACGCCGCUGCCUCCGCCCUCCCCGCGGCACCUGCGGCUGCUGCGGCUGCUGCUCUCCGGCCUCGUCCUCGGCGCCGCCCUGCGUGGAGCCGCCGCCGGCCACCCGGAUGUAGCCGCCUGUCCCGGGAGCCUGGACUGUGCCCUGAAGAGGCGGGCAAGGUGUCCUCCUGGUGCACAUGCCUGUGGGCCCUGCCUUCAGCCCUUCCAGGAGGACCAGCAAGGGCUCUGUGUGCCCAGGAUGCGCCGGCCUCCAGGCGGGGGCCGGCCCCAGCCCAGACUGGAAGAUGAGAUUGACUUCCUGGCCCAGGAGCUUGCCCGGAAGGAGUCUGGACACUCAACUCCGCCCCUACCCAAGGACCGACAGCGGCUCCCGGAGCCUGCCACCCUGGGCUUCUCGGCACGGGGGCAGGGGCUGGAGCUGGGCCUCCCCUCCACUCCAGGAACCCCCACGCCCACGCCCCACACCUCCCUGGGCUCCCCUGUGUCAUCCGACCCGGUGCACAUGUCGCCCCUGGAGCCCCGGGGAGGGCAAGGCGACGGCCUCGCCCUUGUGCUGAUCCUGGCGUUCUGUGUGGCCGGUGCAGCCGCCCUCUCCGUAGCCUCCCUCUGCUGGUGCAGGCUGCAGCGUGAGAUCCGCCUGACUCAGAAGGCCGACUACGCCACUGCGAAGGCCCCUGGCUCACCUGCAGCUCCCCGGAUCUCGCCUGGGGACCAGCGGCUGGCACAGAGCGCGGAGAUGUACCACUACCAGCACCAACGGCAACAGAUGCUGUGCCUGGAGCGGCAUAAAGAGCCACCCAAGGAGCUGGACACGGCCUCCUCGGAUGAGGAGAAUGAGGACGGAGACUUCACGGUGUACGAGUGCCCGGGCCUGGCCCCGACCGGGGAAAUGGAGGUGCGCAACCCUCUGUUCGACCACGCCGCACUGUCCGCGCCCCUGCCGGCCCCCAGCUCACCGCCUGCACUGCCAUGACCUGGAGGCAGACAGACGCCCACCUGCUCCCCGACCUCGAGGCCCCCGGGGAGGGGCAGGGCCUGGAGCUUCCCACUAAAAACAUGUUUUGAUGCUGUGUGCUUUUGGCUGGGCCUCGGGCUCCAGGCCCUGGGACCCCUUGCCAGGGAGACCCCCGAACCUUUGUGCCAGGACACCUCCUGGUCCCCUGCACCUCUCCUGUUCGGUUUAGACCCCCAAACUGGAGGGGGCAUGGAGAACCGUAGAGCGCAGGAACGGGUGGGUAAUUCUAGAGACAAAAGCCAAUUAAAGUCCAUUUCAGACCUGCGG